CUUCCUUGGAGCCCCGCCGCCCGCCGCUCACUCUGCACACGCAGCAGAAGGGACGUGGUGUUCCCCAGGCUCUGGCCCCCCAGGACCUGCGCGGAUCUGGCCCAGGGCGCCUCGCCGACUUCCGUAAACUGGGCGGAGGGAUGAACCCCGACCCAGGGGACGGAGGCGCUCGCCCUCUCGCUGCAGGGUUCUGCCCUCAACACUUCUGGCCCCGCCUGUGAAUGGGGGCCGGAGCGAUGGGGCGGGGCCGGCCUCCCUCCCUCCUCCCAGGCUGACCUCUGCCCUCCUUCGAGCACUUCCCGUUCGGGGUGAUGAUUGAAGAACUGAGUGUGGACAGAGCACCUGUCCUCGCCAGCGCCCAGCUGGAAGCUGAGUUAUUUGUGGCUGCAGCAUUCCAACGCACACACCACCAGAAAUCCCCUUCAGCAUACUGGCCUCAGACCUACCAGGGCAGAGACCUUGUCUUGUUUGCUGCUAGAACCCAGGAUCGCUGGAAAAUCACCUAGCAGCAGCCAGGUGCGGUGACUCACGCCUGUAAUCCCAGCACUUUGGAAGGCCAAGGCGGGUGGAUAGCAAGGUCAAGAGAUCGAGACCAGCCUGGCCAACAUGCUCUGGGCACCUCCAGCUCCUGCUCGCCGGACGGCUCCCAGGGAGAGCAGACGCGCCAGACGCGCCACCCUCGGGGCGCCGACGGUCACGGAGCAUGGGGUCGGCCUUUGAGCGGGUAGUCCGGAGAGUGGUCCAGGAGCUGGACCAUGGUGGGGAGUUCAUCCCUGUGACCAGCCUGCAGAGCUCCACUGGCUUCCAGCCCUACUGCCUGGUGGUUAGGAAGCCCUCAAGCUCAUGGUUCUGGAAACCCCGUUAUAAGUGUGUCAACCUGUCUAUCAAGGACAUCCUGGAGCCGGAUGCCGCGGAACCAGACGUGCAGCGUGGCAGGAGCUUCCACUUCUACGAUGCCAUGGAUGGGCAGAUACAGGGCAGCGUGGAGCUGGCAGCCCCAGGACAGGCAAAGAUCGCAGGCGGGGCCGCGGUGUCUGACAGCUCCAGCACCUCAAUGAAUGUGUACUCGCUGAGUGUGGACCCUAACACCUGGCAGACUCUGCUCCAUGAGAGGCACCUGCGGCAGCCAGAACACAAAGUCCUGCAGCAGCUGCGCAGCCGCGGGGACAACGUGUACGUGGUGACUGAGGUGCUGCAGACACAGAAGGAGGUGGAAGUCACGCGCACCCACAAGCGGGAGGGCUCGGGCCGGUUUUCCCUGCCCGGAGCCACGUGCUUGCAGGGUGAGGGCCAGGGCCAUCUGAGCCAGAAGAAGACGGUCACCAUCCCCUCAGGCAGCACCCUCGCAUUCCGGGUGGCCCAGCUGGUUAUUGACUCUGACUUGGACGUCCUUCUCUUCCCGGAUAAGAAGCAGAGGACCUUCCAGCCACCCGCGACAGGCCACAAGCGUUCCACGAGCGAAGGCGCCUGGCCACAGCUGCCCUCUGGCCUCUCCAUGAUGAGGUGCCUCCACAACUUCCUGACAGAUGGGGUCCCUGCGGAGGGGGCGUUCACUGAAGACUUCCAGGGCCUACGGGCAGAGGUGGAGACCAUCUCCAAGGAACUGGAGCUUUUGGACAGAGAGCUGUGCCAGCUGCUGCUGGAGGGCCUGGAGGGGGUGCUGCGGGACCAGCUGGCCCUGCGAGCCUUGGAGGAGGCGCUGGAGCAGGGCCAGAGCCUUGGGCCGGUGGAGCCCCUGGACGGUCCAGCAGGUGCUGUCCUGGAGUGCCUGGUGUUGUCCUCCGGAAUGCUGGUGCCGGAACUCGCUAUCCCUGUUGUCUACCUGCUGGGGGCACUGACCAUGCUGAGUGAAACGCAGCACAAGCUGCUGGCGGAGGCGCUGGAGUCGCAGACCCUGUUGGGGCCGCUCGAGCUGGUGGGCAGCCUCUUGGAGCAGAGUGCCCCGUGGCAGGAGCGCAGCACCAUGUCCCUGCCCCCCGGGCUCCUGGGGAACAGCUGGGGCGAAGGAGCACCGGCCUGGGUCUUGCUGGACGAGUGUGGCCUAGAGCUGGGGGAGGACACUCCCCACGUGUGCUGGGAGCCGCAGGCCCAGGGCCGCAUGUGUGCACUCUACGCCUCCCUGGCACUGCUAUCAGGACUGAGCCAGGAGCCCCACUAGCCUGUGCCCGGGCAUGGCCUGGCAGCUCUCCAGCAGGGCAGAGUGUUUGCCCACCAGCUGCUAGCCCUAGGAAGGCCAGGAGCCCAGUAGCCAUGUGGCCAGUCUACCAUGGGGCCCAGGAGUUGGGGAAACACAAUAAAGGUGGCAUACGAAGGAAA